GCCAUUCUCGUCCCUGUGCUCAGAGCUCUCAAGCACCCACGAUGGCCUUCUCAGGCCGAGCGCGCCCCUGCAUUAUCCCAGAGAACGAAGAAAUCCCCCGAGCAGCCCUUAACACUGUCCACGAGGCCAAUGGGACCGAGGACGAGAGGGCUGUUUCCAAACUGCAGCGCAGGCACAGUGACGUGAAAGUCUACAAGGAGUUCUGUGACUUUUAUGCGAAAUUCAACAUGGCCAACGCCCUGGCCAGCGCCACUUGCGAGCGCUGCAAGGGCGGCUUUGCGCCCGCUGAGAAGAUCGUGAACAGUAAUGGGGAGCUGUACCAUGAGCAGUGUUUCGUGUGCGCUCAGUGCUUCCAGCAGUUCCCAGAAGGACUCUUCUAUGAGUUUGAAGGAAGAAAGUACUGUGAACAUGACUUUCAGAUGCUCUUUGCCCCUUGCUGUCAUCAGUGUGGUGAAUUCAUCAUUGGCCGAGUUAUCAAAGCCAUGAAUAACAGCUGGCAUCCGGAGUGCUUCCGCUGUGACCUCUGCCAGGAAGUUCUGGCAGAUAUCGGGUUUGUCAAGAAUGCUGGGAGACACCUGUGUCGCCCCUGUCAUAAUCGUGAGAAAGCCAGAGGCCUUGGGAAAUACAUCUGCCAGAAAUGCCAUGCUAUCAUCGAUGAGCAGCCUCUGAUAUUCAAGAACGACCCCUACCAUCCAGACCAUUUCAACUGCGCCAACUGCGGGAAGGAGCUGACUGCCGAUGCACGGGAGCUGAAAGGGGAGCUAUACUGCCUCCCAUGCCAUGAUAAAAUGGGGGUCCCCAUCUGUGGUGCUUGCCGACGGCCCAUCGAAGGGCGCGUGGUGAACGCUAUGGGCAAGCAGUGGCAUGUGGAGCAUUUUGUUUGUGCCAAGUGUGAGAAACCCUUUCUUGGACAUCGCCAUUAUGAGAGGAAAGGCCUGGCAUAUUGUGAAACUCACUAUAACCAGCUAUUUGGUGAUGUUUGCUUCCACUGCAAUCGUGUUAUAGAAGGUGAUGUGGUCUCUGCUCUUAAUAAGGCCUGGUGCGUGAACUGCUUUGCCUGUUCUACCUGCAACACUAAAUUAACACUCAAGGAUAAGUUUGUUGAAAUUGACCUAAAGCCAGUCUGCAAACACUGUUAUGAGAAAAUGCCAGAAGAAUUUAAGAGGCGACUUGCCAAACGGGAGAGAGAAGCAAAGGAUAAGGACAAGCAGAAAAAGAAAAAGCCAGUCUGUUUGUAAACUUUUCUAUCCCUGUGUCAUCAUUUUCACUGCUUUCUCCUUUGGAAUAAGUUUGUGGAGUUUGACAUGAAGCCAGUCUGUAAGAAGUGCUAUGAGAAAUUUCCAUUGGAGCUGAAGAAAAGACUUAAGAAACUAGCUGAGACCUUAGGAAGGAAAUAAGUUCCUUUAUUUUUUCUUUUCUAUGCAAGAUAAGAGAUUACCAACAUUACUUGUCUUGAUCUACCCAUAUUUAAAGCUAUAUCUCAAAGCAGUUGAGAGAAGAGGACCUAUAUGAAUGGUUUUAUGUCAUUUUUUUAAUUAAAAAAGAAAAAUUCAUAUAAUCGUGUUUAAAACACAAAUGAAGUCAGUAUUUGCCUUUGUUAACCCUUAUCCAUUUGUUGACAUGUAGACUGUUUACAAAAAAAAAACACAUGGUUAAAUGUUAAAUUUUAAUUAAGGCCCCCAAAAAUUAAAUAUAACUUUUUAAAAUGAAAGGAGUCACCUUUUACAUGACUCAGGUGAAAAAACAGUAUAAACAUUAAUUUACUUUGUGUUCAAAAGAAAAUUCCAACUGCUGUUGGGGAAGGACACAGAAAAGAAAAAUAACCACCCAAGAAAAACAAAAACAAGAAAAACAAAUCUUAUACAAUCUUAGUAUAUUUAUCAAACUAGUAGCUAGAAAGUGAAUAUGCACAUUACUAAGACAAAAAACAAGUGUAAUUCAGAACUACUUGAUUUUUUUUAGUUAAAUGCAAUAAUUAUUAUGCUUAGUUUUAUAACCUGCUCUCCUUGUGAAUUCUUCCUUCAAAUGAUUACUUAACGCAGUAGUAAUAGCUAGCUGUAGGAUGUCCUUUAAAUUUUUGUGCAAAAAAAAAUUUAUACCAGGUAUUUGGAAAUAUACUUUACAAUAUUGGAAAAUGAAGUAUUUUUAAUGUAUUACAGCAAUUAUGUUUCUAAGCUUAAUGUUAAGCAUGUAGUCUUAGAAUAGGACAUGAAAUUAAAUUGUAUGUAGCUUGGAAUAUAUUGCUUCAGAAAACUGAAUGUGUAUGUCGGUCAUAUUGCCUUUAUAACCAUGCUAAUAUCUAUGCUUUAUACAUACUCAAACUUGCCUUGCCUUAAAAACAUACAUACUACAUACUUAAAUCAGGAAUUCUAGCCAUCUCACAGAAUACCAACUAAAACUAAGUGCAUUGAGAUCUGAGAUUGGUAAACCCAGAUUCAUUUACCACAGCUGUAAUUAAGUUUUUAGAAACUAUUCUCUUUUUGGGGAAAUCCAUUGAAGUUAAUUUCUGUUAUCUUAUUAGAAGAAAAUGAUGUUGAUAUGUGUUUCAGAUUUUCCAUUUGAAAUCUUAUAAUUAAUUUGAUUUAUUUACUGUAAGUAGGAGGUAUAAAUGACACUCUUAAAUUGGAAGGAGGGGUGUUUUAGUGUCUGUUUUAGGUCAAAAUUAGUGAUUCUAUUUUUAUCAAAAGUUUUAUCCUGAAGUUUCAGGACCACUCUUCCUUAAUAAACUUGUUAAUGGAAAGCGAGCUUUAUGAACAUUUAAAAAUGUUGCUGCUGCUUUGUUGCUUAAAAAGAAAGUUGCCAAGAGAGACUUCUUAGGGAAAAUAUUUGGGUUUUUUUUCCAAAAAUUGCUGAAAUAUUGUUUUGCCAUUUUUAAAAAGUCUCAGGUUAUUACCACUCUGCCAUUAAAUAUUUGUAUGCCUGCAUUUUUAAAAAUUCUGUGCAUGUACUUUAUGGAGUACAUUCUAUUUUUGUUUUCAGAUACCCUACAACCAAUUUUUUUUAGUAAUCUUUUAGAAUUGAAAUUAUCAUAAAUGAUCGAGAAUAAUCAUCACAUAGUUUAAGAUUGUAUAUGUUGAGUAGUUUAAAACAAUCUUUGCAUUUUACAGUAAGAAUCAAAGUCCCUUCAGUGUGCCUUUGUCAGCUAAUAUGUGACCAGCAAUGACAACCUUGGGAGUAUUUAUUAAAUAUUAUGCUAUGAAUAUAGGCAACACAGAACAGGGUUUGCAGUAUAGCGUCUUGAUGCUAAAUUCUCAUAUACCUCUACACGAGAAAUAUGGAGGAGAAAAACAAGCAUUUACAUAUAUUCUUCGUCACUUUGAAGAUGCAUGGCCUGAACUCGACUGCUUGUGUUUGUUUACAUAUCAGGCAUACCCAGGCAUCUCCUGCAGCCAGAGGUUCCAUUGCUGUCUUUGCUCAGUCCUCUUUUAAAAUAUGAAUUAGUGGACAGGCACGGUGCCUCACACCUGUAAUCCCAGCACUUUGGGAGGUCGAGGCAGGUGGAUCACGAGGUCAGGAGAUCAAGACCAUCCUGGCUACCACUGAAACCCCAUCUCUACUACAAAAAAAUUAGCCGGGCGUGGUGGCGGGCACCUGCAGUCCCAGCUACUCGGGAGGCUGAGGCAGGAGAAUGGUGGGAACCCGGGAGGCAGAGCUUGCAGUGAGCCAAGAUCACGCCACUGCACUCCAGCCUGGGCAACAGAGCAAGACUCUGUCUCAAAAAAAAUAAAUAAAUAAAUUAUGAAUGAGUAUUUUCUAGAAAUUCAACUUGCUAAGCCUGUAAUACUUAAGGGUAGUUUAUCUAGAUACAGUACUUUCUUCCCUGAUAAGUAGUAUCAUUGGAGCCCUUAGGUAUAGGAGAAGAGGAAGAAGUUUAAAAAGUGUAAGUGGGCCGGGCGUGGUGGCUCAUGCCUGUAAUCCCAGCACUUUGGGAGGCCGAGGGGGGCGGAUCACGAGGUCAGGAGAUCCAGACUAUCCUGGCUAACAAGGUGAAACCCCGUCUCUACUAAAAAUACAAAAAAAAACAUUAGCCAGGCGUGGUGGCGGGCGCUUGUAGUCCCAGCUACUCGGGAGGCUGAGGUAGGAGAAUGGCUUGAACCCAGGAGGCGGAGCUUGCAGUGAGCCGAGAUUGCACCACUGCACUCCAGCCUGGGCGACAGAGCAAGACUCCGUCUCAAAAAAAAAAAAAAAGUGUAAGUGGAUUAAAAGAGAAACUUGGUCUAGUUCAUAAUAUUUUUAAUAGGGCUUUCCCUGGCUGCUGGAAAACUUAGGCCAGUAAGCAUCUCUUUGUUUAAAGUCCUACAAGACAAUUUGAAAUAAUUCAUUGUUCAUGCCAAAAUUCUAAGUACUGUUUUUCUUAGCAAGUGUAACAUAAUCAGGAACAAUGGGUACAAGUAAAACAUUCUUUGGAUGAUAUUCAAAGCCUUAUUAGCACUGCACCUGAAUAAUAGGUCAUUUUGCCUCACUCAUUUGCCAAAGUAGCCAUUUCUAAGUUAAGGAAGUUUUUAGAUAGGCUCAUAGCCUUGUAUUUCGUUUUAGAUUGUAAGCUCAAUGGCAGGGAUACUAUAUUGGUAAUUAUGUUUUCAUAUAGCAACCACCACAGUAUAUUCUUGGUGCUUAAUAAAUGUUUAUAAUUGUUAACAAUAA